AGUCGGACUCUGUUCCUUUAUUAUACUAUACCUGGUGUUAGGUUUUUAGAGCACUUAAAUUUUUUUUGUCUUUUUGCUUUACUCUAAUAAAUAUUCUAGUUAACAUUAAUAUCUAGCUUAAUAUGAUUUAAAUGUAUGUUAAAAUUCUUAAGAGUAGUAGCAAAUCUAGAUUGGGAACUGGAUCUGUAGACAAUAUUCAAAAGAUACAAUUCAGAUGACCCUGAACACCAGUAAACUGAUCCAGGGGCCAAAUAUUCUCUCAAAAUAGAGGAGGAAAAAGGAAAAGAGGCAUGUAGGGACCCAGAAGAAGAAGGGCGAUUUAUGUGGAGUGGAGGGAAUUUUCAUGUUAAACCACAGGUAGGGCUUGUUUACUUUGUCACAUUUUCCCUGUAAUAGAGAAACUGCUGAGCCAGAAUUGUGCAACUGAUUGAAUUAGCACCUUGUUUAAAUUGUUAGCAUCCAUCUUUGAGAAGCAUGUAUUUUAGAUUAAAGAUUUAAAAAUCUUGGCUGAAACAAAGGACAAUCUCUUUCCUUUAUGAAGUUGUUCAUUGAACUUUAAAUAGUAAGAUAUUAACAGAUGAGGAUUGAAUUUAGUCUUCAAAUAAGCAUCUCUGUGAUUUGUUGGUCACAGUAUGAUCUCUUUCCCAUCCCCCACUAUUUUUUACUUUUGAUAGGGCAAACUCUUAUGUUUUCAUGAAAUAUUUAAAGCAAAUGAUGUGUUAAUUAUGUUUAGUUAUCCUUUUUGAGAGUUCUCUAGCUUUUUCUGUUCUGAGGUUCAGAAUCAAUAUAAGGACAUAUUGAAAUCAUAAUUGCAUUUUAUCUUCCAAACAGCCAUUGAAAAUAAUUGCAUUUUAAUUUGAGAAUUUUAUCUCAACUCCAUAUAACAGCUUAUACUUUAAAAUAUAAUCCAGAGGUACAGUACUUUUCAGUUCAUUUAUUAGCUUUGUCAGUUUCCACAUUUGUAAAGUUGAACAUUUACUGAAAUUAUGGGCUGGUUUGGGUUAAAAUGAAGUAACAUAUGUGAAGCAUCUUAGAUGGUCACACAUAGUAGGCUCUCGGUAAUUAGUCGUUGCUGCUGUUGUUAUGGGUAUUUAAUUAACUUGGAUUUCUAGGGCACCAUUUGUUAGAGUGCAGUGAACCAAUUCUGAAUUCUACCCUCCUAUAUUUGUUACUUGUUUAGACUGACUUAACCACUGUGGAGAAUAAAGCCUAUUUGUGGGGGUUGGGGUGGGGGUGGUGCCUACUGACUCUUAUAUGCAUGUUUUUUCAGAGUUACAGGAUGUGUACUGGAAUGUGAAGGAUUAAGCUUUGUGGUGGCAUGUUCUAUAUGGUCAUCCAUAGUGACCAAACUAAUUUGGAAUGUUGUUUUGUUACUAACUUGGAAAUGUGUUAUUUUCUCUACAGAGGAUGUUGAUCUGAAUAAACUGCUUAUUAUGCUUUAUACAUUUCUAGAGCGAGAGGAACUGUCAAUCAGUGUAAAUCUCACCCAGCACAGUAUUUUCUUUCACAAACAUGGGGAGGAGGCAAUACCAAGAUAACCACUUUUGGGACAGAGCCAGGAGCUGUUGUGUAACUCAGAGGGUGUGUGAUAGCAUCCAGCUUUGGAGCCCAUCACGUCACAUUGAGAAAUUGUGGCAGGGAGGCUUACAGGAAAAACAUCUUGUUUAUUAACACCUGAAUAUGUUACUUAUGUAGCUUUUUAAAAGUCAUCAGUUAGCUAGCUUCUCAAAGAGAGGCAAGAACCCAUUCGCGUAGUUACAGAUUGUGGCUAUAGUAAGUCUUCUGGUAACAGGAGCUGUGAGCACCACUUCUUCAGUGAAGUCUUUCCUGUUCCCUUCUCCACUCAGGUUGAUGACUGUCUCCUUUGUACCUGGUUGCAGCUUGAACAUAUUUAGGUAACUUCUCUCAAAGCACUUGAAACAUGCUACUGCCCAUGUCUCCUUUCCAGCUUGUCUGUAAACUCCUUGAUGGUAGCAGCUGUGUGUGUAAGUGCCACUGAGUAUAGAUUCCUGGAGCUUAGGUUGAUCCCCAGUAAAUGUUAAAUGCAGGUCUCCCUGUGCCUGUGGAAAUGCCUCAACAUCAAUUGGUUCAAUUGUAUCCUUCAACUUGAUCACUAACAGGUCUUUAAUGAAAAGUCUCCAGAGAUGCUAUUCCCAUUCUGUACUAUCCUCAUCAUUACCAUUCUUAUUUCUUCUUUGCCAAUGCAAAUUCUCUAUUUCAUUUUUUUCUUUAAGUACUUCUCUAUGAAGCUUUUUAAAAGUAUGCUUCAUUUUAGGGCCAGACAUGGUGGCUCAUGCGAGGCCCAUGCGGGUGGAUCACCUGAGGUCAGGAGUUUAAGACCAGCGUGACCAGCAUAGUGAAACCCCAUCUCUACUAAAAAUACAAAAUUAGUCGGGUGUGGUGGCGUGCACCUGUAAUCCCAGCUACUCAGGAGACUGAGGCAGGAGAAUUGCUUGAACCCAGGAGGCAGAGGUUGCAGUAAGCUGAGACACCGCAGCCUGGGGGACAGAGUGAGACUCCAUCCCAAAAAAUAAAAAUAGAAGUAUGCUUCAUUUUAGUUAGUUUAUAAUCAACAUUGAGAAAUCCAAGAAAGGUGAGAAAUGUAAACUAGAGCUGGAGAUUUAAAAUUGGCACCUGUAAAAAUACAUUAUUUUUUGAAGUAAAAAAAGUUUGUAAACAUUUCCCUUGUUUACAAAUCUGAAAUUAUAUUAAUUUUGGUAAAAUUCUAGAUUUUUUCCAAAUAAGUCAAAACCUCAAAAGAAUGGAAAUUUUAGGUAAAAUUUAGGUAAAAAUGGAAAGAAAGUAAGAGUCAUAAUUUUCAGGCUGUUAUAAGAAAUGUCUUUUACUGUAUCAUAUGGUAUUUUAUAGUAUAUAAAAAUAUAGGAAUUGACCUUAUUAUCCUUAGUGUACAAGGUUUUAUUGUGGUUUAAAAUUCCAAGUCUUCGAUGUAGCUUCCUUUAUUCUUCUUCUUCAGUUACACCAUAAUAGUUUAUUGAAAUUUGAUGCAUAUAGGAAAAAACCUUGUAAUUGACUUUUUUUGGAGAAAAAUUAUUCAUUUUAAGACAAAAGCAGAGAUUGUUUGAGCCAAAACCUGAUGGAUUUAAGAGUGCUGUUGAUCAUGGUUGACUUGUGAAAGUGAUAGAUAGAUAGAUAGAUAGAUAGAUAGAUAGAUAGAUAGAUAGAUAGAUCUCUUAUCGUUAUUUUUCUUUUAUACUGGGCUUAUGUUUUUUUUUUCUUAUUUUCUUGCUUAAUAAUAGUAUCAUUAAGCAGGCAGGAGAAAAAUAAUACCAUUGAAACUAAAAGUUAGUAAUUUAAUUUGAUUAUGUAUAUAUAUAUUUUAUUAUACUUUAAGUUCCGGGAUACAAGUGCAGAACGUGUAGGUUUGUUGUAUAGGUAUACGUGUGCCAUAAUGGUGUCCUGCACCUAUCCCCCCAUCAUUUAGGUUUUAAGCCCCACAUGCAUUAGCUAUUUGUCCUAGUGUUCUCCCUCUCCUUGCCCCCCACCUGCUGACUGGCCCCAGUGUGUGAUGUUCCCCUUCCAGUGUCCACGUGUUCUCGUUGUUUAACUCCCACUUAUGAGUGAGAACAUGCGGUAUUUGGUUUUCUGUUCUUGUGUUAGUUUGUUGAGGAUGAUGGCUUCUAGCUUCAUCCAUGUCCCCACAAAAGACGUGAACUCAUUCUUUUUUAUGGCUGCACGGUAUUCCAUGGUGUAUAUGUACUACAUUUUCUUUAUCCAGUCUAUCAUUGAUGGGCAUUUGGGUUGGUUCCAUGUCUUUGCUAUUGUAAAUAGUGCUGCAGUAAACAUAUGUGUGCAUGUGUCUUUAUGGUAGAAUGAUUUAUAUUCCUUAGGGUACAUACCCAGUAAUGGGAUUGCUGGAUCAAAUGGUAUUUCUGGUUCUAGAUCCUUGAGGAAUCGCCACCCUGUCUUCCACAAUGGUUGAACUAAUUUACCCUCCCACCGACAGUGUAAAAGCAUUCCUAUUUCUCCACAGCCUCACCAGCAUCUAUUGUUUCUUGACUUUUUGAUCAUCGCCAUUGUGACUGGCGUGAGAUGGUAUUUCAUUGUGGUUUUGAUUUGCAUUUCUCUAAUGAUCAGUGAUGUUGAGCUGUUUUUCAUAUAUUUGUUGGCUGCAUAAAUGUCUUCCUUUGUGAAGUGUCUAUUUAUAUCCUUUGCCCACUUUUUGAUGGGGUUGUUUUUUUCUUGUAAAUUUGUUUAAGUUCCUUGUAGAUUCUGGAUAUUAGACCUUUGUCAGAUGGGUAGCUUGCAAAAACGUUUUGCCAUUCUGUAGGUUGCCUGUUCACUCUGAUGGUAGUUUCUUUUGAUGUAGAGAAGCUCUUUAGUUUGAUUAGAUCCCAUUUGUCAAUUUUUGCUUUUGUUGCAAUUGCUUUUGGCAUUUUAAUCAUGAAGUCUUUGCUCAUGCCUAUAUCAUAAUUUUGCAGUUUAUUAUAUUUAUGGACAAAGUAACAAGAAUAGUAUUUGUUCUGUGGCAUUUGUUUUAUGUAUUUUGUCAUACAUUGUACCCACAUACAAAUAUAUAUAUAUAUAUUUACAGUAAAUAUAUGUUAACAUCUUAAUGCUUAUGAAUUUUCAAAUGAUACAUAGUAGCAUUGAUUUUUACCUGUAAUCAUACGUGGAAAACUUACCUUUAAAUGACGGAGACCUUUACAUAUAUGCGUAGUUUGCACAUUAUCAGUUGAAGCUAGUACAUCUUUAUUUAGUACUCUAUUUUUCCGAACACCACUUUUCUAGUUUCUGUGGGAGAUGUAAUGAUGUAUGUACCCUUUAGAGGAUCACAGUCUCAGAGCAACUCUUACAGCACCACAGAGCUCUAGAACAGGAAGAAACUCUGGAGGUUAUCUUCUCUUAGGGGUAUGUUUAAACAGUAGUUCACUGAUUCUUACGCAUUUUCUCCUUUGCUCAGUAAGCAGGAGAUGUGGGCCAAUUUUUUGUUUGUUUGUUUGUUUGUUUGUUUGAAACAGGGUCUCACUCUGUUGCCCAGGCUAGAGUGCAGGGGCACAGUCACUGCUCACUGCAGCCUCUACCUACCAAGCUUAGGUGAUCCUCUCACCUUAGCCUGGGACUACAGGCUAGUGCCACCAUGCCCAGCUGACUUCUUUUACUUUUACUAGAGAUGAGGUUUCACUAUGUUGCCCAGGCUGGUCUCAGAUUCCUGAGCUCAAGUGAUCCCCCUGCGUUGGCCCCCCAAAGUGCUGAGAUUACAGGAGUGAGCUAUCAUGUCCAGCCAUGGGGCAGUUUUUUUGGGCCAGGGAUUUACAAAUUAUGAAGUCAAGAAAUAAUUUUAGUGGGAAAUGACUAGAAUAUAACACUUGUUUUUCCUGUAAUUACGUUAGAGACUACCAAAGCAUAUUGCAGAUUAUUUCCAAUAUAUCAUAUUAUAUUGUGUAUAUGUAUACUGGGUUUUAAAAAAUGUAUUAUAGGUUGGGCACAGUGGCUCACACCUAUAAUCCCAGCACUUUGGGAGGCCGAGGCAAGUGGAUCACCUGAGGUCAGGAGUUCAAGACCAGCCUGGGCAACAUGGUGAAACCCUGUCUCUCCUAAAAAUACAAAACGUAGCUGGGCGCAGUGGCACAUGCCUGUAAUCCCAGCUACUCAGGUGGCUGAGCAGGAGAAUUGCUUGAGCCCGGGAAGCAGAGGUUGUAGUGAAUUGAGAUUGCGCCAUUCCAUUGCAGCCUGGGCAACAGAGCAAGACUGCCUCAAAAAAAAAAAAAGUAUUCUAAAUUUUUAAAUACUUUUUUAAAUGUAUUUUUUUAUUGAAGUGAAAAGAUUUUAGAAAACAUAUCUUUAAUGUGUCUUCUCCUCCACCUCCCACCCCCCACUUGAAACCUGGAGAGCAGCCAUUGUUCUUCAUCCCGAGAUAUGCAGCUUAAUCUCUUUGCUGUGCUCUCUUGCUGUCAUGCCUGACACCAAAGUCAAGCAUUUUCUACCCAGAAACCAGGUGAUAUUUCCCUGUGAUAGUAAAAAAUAUGCAGUGAGAUCAUUUUUUCAUUAUGCUGGUCUUCCUUGCAGCCUUUGGGCAAAAAUAAAACACUUUGGUGGCUCUGUUAAUCUGUAGGUAUUGCUUAUGAUGUGCCUAACUUGGUACCAAGAUGCGAUUUAGUCACCAAGAGAAUUUGGAUUAUUUAAUACUCGUACAUAAUAAAACUCCUCAUCAAAUAUUCAUGUGGGCACAUACAGAGGCCUAAUUGUAUUCUUGUAAUGCACAAUAUAAAUACUAAUAUUGUUUUGGAGAAUCAGCAUGGUAUGCUGAAGCCAUGGUUUGGAAAAAUGCAUUGUAGUAUGUUUUUAUCUGUGGGAAUUACUGGCAAAUAUAAUUGAGAGAUUCUAAAUACUGUAGUUGUUUCCUUCACUUUUGAACUUGGCUUAAGUAUUUUUGGUCUUUUUUUUUUUUUUAAAUCGCUGAAUUAUUGUUUUGUUGUAUCAACGGUUGAAGCUAAACCAUGAUUGUUAUUUUAAUAUUUAUGUCUUCUUUUAAAGAUAUAAUUUAAAAACAAUUUUCUCCCACUGAGAGGGAUUAAAAAAUAAACGGGGAGAAUAGUAGAAUAAAUGCUCAGGUGCCCAUUCCUCAGCUCAAACAUUUAUGAAACCAUUGUUACCCACCCUCUUUCUGCAGGUCCCAAUUAUUUUUGAGUCAUUUUCUUUGUCACAACAUUUCACCUGUAAAUACUUCAGUAUGCAUUUGUAAGAGACAAGGACUUCCGUUUUUAGAUAGAUAAAGAAGAAUCUUAAAAACCUUUUUGAAGAAUAUACUGAAUUAUGAUAAUUAAAUUUGUGUAUGGGAUGUUAGAGCGAUAUAAAGGAAAAUGAGAUAGCUUAAAUGGAGUAAGUGGAAAAAAGAAAUACCGACAAGCAAUUGUACCAAGAAAUAGUAGAAAAGGUGUGAAAAGGCCAAUUAACAGCUUUUAAAGUACUCAUGGAGAAAAGGAAGACAUUUGCAUUUUUUAACAGGCAGUAUGUGUCUGCAUUCCACAUAGGUCAGUAGGGGAGUAAAGCCAAGUGUAUUUCAUACCAUUUGAAAUAGCAAUUCUGUUUCAAGACUUUUUCUUAAGGGAGAAAUCAAAGAUGUGUACAAAGAUUGCCAAUCAAGGUAUUCACUACAAUAUUACUUAUAGAAAUGAGGAAUUGAACCUUUUUUUAAAGAGAUCUUUUAGUCCGUUCUUUUAUUUUUAUAGAUAAUAGUACAGGUAGUUUCCAUUUAUUAAGUACUUGCCAUAUUUCAAGCAUUUUGCUAACACCUUAACAUGAAUUAUAUGACAUAAACCUCUAACAACAAUAAUAAAUAAGCAAUAUUUAUUACAACCUCCAACUUUCACAUGAGAAACUAAGGCUUAGGCCGGGUGCAGUAGUGUACUCCCAGCACUUAGGGAGGCCAAGGCAGGCAGAUCACCUGAGGUCAGGAAUUCAAGAGCAGCCUGGCCAACAUGGCAAAACUUUGGCUCUACUAAAAAUACAAAAAUUAGUCAGGUGUGGUGGCAUGUGCCUGUAGCCCCAGCUACUCAGGAGGCUGAGGCAGGAGAAUCACUUGAACUUGGGAGGUGGAGGUUGCCGUGAACUGAGAUCAUGCCACUGCACUCCAGCCUGGGCGGCAGAGUGAAACUCUGUCUCAAAAAAAAAAAAGAUAGAAAGAAACUAAGGCUUGAGUUUAACUAACUUGUCCUAGAUAACUCAGGAAAUAAUCAUAAAGGAGAGUUCUAGACUUAACCUAAUUCCAGAGCCUUUGUAUCUAAACAUUAUACUGUACUACUUCCUGACCUAGUCAAAAAGGCGAUUUAGGCCCAUAGUAAGAAAUGUGAAGAAGGGACUUUGCUCCAGGUCACAAGAAAUAAUGCAACAGUGAGGUUGAAAAAUCCUAACUCAGGGCUAAAUACAAUCUGUUGCCUCCCUGCAUGAAUAUGGCUAAUAAAAAUAAUUGUUUCUUAUUUCUUCUCUUUAGUAUCCUAUAUUCAACAUUUCCCCAUCUACUAUUUAUGAAAUUAUAAGUUUCUAGUCUUUAUUUUCUUCUCUGAGGAAUAAUUUUCUAAAUUAUAGUUGCUCAGCAACAUUCAUGAAAUAGCACUGCAGUACUCAUUUCCUGAGCCUAAAGGAAUUGAACUUAAUGCUCAAUAUUAGUGGAAUGAUUAAAUGAAGAUAAUAUAUUUAUAAAAUAAUGUUUUGUAACCACUAGAUAUUGUACAAUAUGAUUCCGGUUGUAUACAGUGUAUACAGUGUUUAAUUUAUGUAGGAAGACCUGACAGAAAUUAACCCAGAUGGUAAAAUGAAUUCAUAGUGGCUACCUCUAGGUGUUAGAAUUAUGAGGAAUUUUUAUUUCUUCAUUACUUUUUUGGGAAAUUGUUGCAAAUGUUAUCAGCAUUUGUGGUAUAAGUUAAUAAAUAUUACCAUUAUUGAGUACUUACUGUGUGUCAAGCACUGUUUAAGCACUUUUCAUCUUUUACACUUAGUUCUGAAAAUAGCCCUAAGAGAUUUUAUUAUCCUUAUUGUAUAGAUGAGGAAACGGAGAUUGAAUACUGAGACAAUUUGAGUGUAUCCUUCUAGGUGUGUUCUUGGCUUCCAAAUGUAUUUUUUUUCACUUUGUAAAAAUGUAUGUGGAAUAUUAUCGCAAAGUAGUCAAUAUAUUUUUAAAAAAAUUGAUGGAUGACAUUUCAUCUUAGGAAUGUGCCAUGAUUUUUUUUCAACUGGUCCUUUUUGUUCUUUGCCUCUACUGCAAUAUUCUGCUCAUAGGAAUAAUAGUACAAUGAACGUCUUUGCAAAUAAAUUUGUGUGUGCAUGUCUGAUUAUCUUUCUAGAAUAAGCUCUUAGAAAUGGAGUUACUGGGUCAAAGAUCAUAAACAUUUUAGAGGCUUUUGGUACAAGUUGUGAGAUUGCAGGUGACAAAUGACCUUCUUUCCUUAAAUUUAGAAAAGUUGUUUUGGGGCUAUAAAUUUGGGAGAAAUGGGUCAUCUAAAUCAUCUGUGGGAAUUUGUGCUUUCAUAGUUUCUGUUACAGAAGUCAGGCUUCUCUAAGCUUGCUGGAGGCAGUGAACACAGAGAAAAAGAGGAAAGACAAACUUUGGAGAUUAAAUUGUAGCUACUUACUUGCUUUAUGACCUUGAGCAGCUAUUUAUUCAUUUUUCUCUUCUAGUUAACAUUUUUAUUAACUUAGAAACCUUUUCAUUGCAAUUGUUUUAUAUAAACAUGUAAAAUAUAGCUAUCAUCUAUACACAUUUUCUCUGAUGUUUGAUCUUAUAGGACCUUAGGGUCAUAAUUAGAUAGCAUAAGUUCCAUUGUAUAAUUAAAAAAACUAUACAUAUAAAAGGUUAACACAUUGAUUACAGAUGACCCUAGAAAGCAUUUUAGAUGUUGCAUCUUUAAAUUAAAAAGAAUUUUUCUAAGGGGUCACAUGUUCCCUUCCUCUGACAAGCAAGAACAGAAAAUUUUGGAUGAAUUAAUUGAAAUUUUUGUUAAAUAGUUAAAGAUUUAUUGUGUGUUUCUCGUGGGCGUAUCAUCUUCCAGAGACUUUGUAGGCAACUUCUGGAGACUUUAAUUAUAGGUUUGGGUGGUAGGGAGAAGAGCAUUUUAACUUAAGGGAGUCCAGAGAAUCAUUAAUGAAAUCAGUAAAGAAAGUCUCCAUAUGAAGCCACUGAAUACAUUAGGGUUGGUUAUUCUAGGAAAACCAUGUUGAUAAUGGGUAAUCUGAUAGUCCAGAAAUUCAUGAGCAGUACAAAUGGAAUAAACAGAAAACAUUCUAUUGAGGGUUGAAGGCUGUAAUUGGUUUAAUGGAAAAAAAAGAAGUACUACUUUUUACUACGAAUAGUAAAAUUGUAAAACAAUCUACUGGCCGGGCGCGGUGGCUCACGCCUGAAAUCCCAGCACUUUGGGAGGCCGAGGCAGGCAGAUCACGAGGUCAGGAGAUCGAGAUCAUCCUGGCUAACACAGUGAAACCCCAUCUCUACUAAAAAUACAAAAAAAAAAAAAAAUUAGCUGGGCACGGUGGCGGGCACCUGUAGUCCCAGCUAGUCGGGAGGCUGAGGCAGGAGAAUGGCUUGAACCCGGGAGGCGGAGCUUGCAGUGAGCCGAGAUUACGCCACUGCACUCCAGCCUGGAUGACAAAGAGUGAGACUCCGUCUCAAAAAAAAAAAAAAAAAGAAAAAAAGAAAUUAAAAAACCUACUAUAAAUGGUAGGCAUAGAAAAUAAGUAUAAGGAGGAUUUUUAUCAGAGGCUCUUAAUCCAUAAUUAAUGGUUGGAUUAGGAGGGCUCAACUCUUCAAAGUUAUAGAAAUGUGCUUUUUGGAAGAUGACAUCUCCACCUCUUUCAAAUUUCUAAAGCAGUAACUCCAAAAGGCUUAAGCUCCCACUGGAAUGUAAACUCCGCAAGGAUAGGGAUUUUUGUUUUAUUCACUUUUUUUUCCCUCAUACUGGCAGAUAGUUCUGCUUAAUAAAUAUUUGUCGAGUGUAUGAUUUCUGUAAACUUAUGUGUGGUGUACUUAUAGUAAUAGAUUUUUAGAAGUUAGGAGUGUAUGUAGUAAAUCCCAGAUUGAUGUCUUAACUGGGCUACUUCUGAAUUUGUCCAAAAAUUUUCUCUUGGUACUUAACUCUAGAUGUAGAAUGGAAAGAUUUAUAUGAUAAAUUUGUAGUUGAAUUCCAUUUUUCUGUGCCAACAUGAAAAUGUAGUAUGAAAAUUAUUCUAAAAAUACAUAUUCAUUCAUCAGUGUAUAAGAAAAUGUACCACUGUGAUGCUGUUUUCAUUUGAUUUAAUGAAUGAAACUGUUACAGAAAACUUCCUCUUAAAAUUGUGAAUGGAAAAUUUGCUGCUUGUUUUCAUUAGAUCAAGUAAUAUGACAAUAACUGCUGUUCUGGCUGAAAAUGUAAAGUCAAUAAAAUGUUGACAAAUUCACCUGCAGAGAACAUUGCUUUAUCAGCAAGAAAUUUAGAUUUUUGCAGUGAAGCCCAAAUAUUAUGGCUGAGUAUCAUUACACAGCAUUUUUAGCAGGUCAUGUAAUAUAAUCUGUAAUUAUAUUAGUCAGUGUAGUAUGUUUCCAUACUUUUUAAAAUUGAAAUUUGGGAGAAGGUUAAAAAGAGGCUGGCCGCGGUAGCUCACACUGUAAUCCCAGCACUUUGGGAGGCUGAGGUGGGUGGAUCACUUGAGGUCAAAAGUUCAAGACUAGCCUGGCCAACAUGGUGAAACCCCAUCUCUACUAAAAAUACAAAAAAUUAGCCAGGCAUGGUGGCACACGCCUGUAAUCCUAACUACUUGGGAAGCUGAGGUAGGAGAAUCACUUGAAUAUGGGAGGCAGAGGUUGCAGUGAGCCAACAUCGUGCCACUGUACUCCAGCCUGGCAACAGAGUGAGACUCCAUCUCAAAAAAAAAAAAAAAAAAAAAAAUUGACUAAGAGAAGGUUAAAUGCAAGUUCAUUUUUAAAAAAAUUUAAAAAUUAUAGCAUUUGUCAAGAGAAAAAGUGAAUUACUUAGCAAUUGAAGAGUGAUAAAACCACUGAUAAUUUUACAAAUCAUGAAUUUUCUUUGGUAAUUAAAGGGAUGACCAUAAAUAUUUUUUUAAAAUGAUUUUUACCAGUCAGAUAUAAACAAUAUUUGACUAAUUGCUUGCUGCCUGCGCUUGAUUAUUUGUGAGCAAAUUUUUCUUGUUUUACACCAUCUUUGGCAGAUUAAAGAAGUUACUGCAUUUUGUUUUCUAUAAUUAUUUUGGUAUUACAGGAACUACAAUCAUUUUAAAUUUAUUUGAAAACGAUUGCAUCCUCACUCUAAAAGGCUGUCAGAACACUUGUGUCAUUUUGGUUUUUGCAUCAUUUUAAGAGGCCUUGCAAGAUUCCCAGAAUUAAUUUUAGUAGAAUGGCAGGAAUUGACCUUCAUAGAUUCCAUAUCUUAAAGUGCGGUUUCUAGCUUUAGUUGAAAUAUGAAUUUCUAAGUCACCACACCCUCUAGUAUUCAAGUAUAAUGUAAAAUACAUUUUGAAGUUAGAUUUAGAGUUUUGAGCUUGGAUCUUUGAGGUAAUUUACCAUAAUCUUUUUACCUGGUGGCAUAAUCCCUUUUAUAACAUUCUGUAAGAAUGUUAACAUUCCUAACAACUGUUGCCUAAAGACUCACGGAGCAGGGACCCCAAUCUUUUAUGAAGCAGUCUUCGUAUUACUUACAUACUAAUUAAGUCGUUUUUCCUUAUGUUGAGCUCAAAUUUACCAUAUGCCAGGCACCAUAACUUCUCUGUUCAAUUCGAAUUGUGGAGUAUUCCCGGCAUACAGACAAGUAUUGCGAAUACUAUAUUGAACAUCUCUGAAAGUCAUUUACCCUUAAUUUUUGCUCUAUUUGCUUGGGAUUGUUGUUUCCUGUGUUAAUGUAUAUCAGAGACACAUACAUCAAAUGUCUUCCUAAAAUUAAGAUAAAUUUGUGGCAUUUCUGUUAUUAUUCUAGAAAUUCUGUUCAGAAAGGAAAGAGGUUCACGUGUUAUUUGAACACCCAUUCAGCUUUCUUUUGCUUUGUGUACUGAAGUGAAGCGAGGCUUUCCGCCCCCCUCCCCCCUCACCCCCCCCCCCCCCGACCUCAUUUGCCCUGAGGCCCUCCCAAGCACCAGAGCUGGACCACUGUUCACUAUUUAUUACACAUGGAAGCUUCCACAUUAUUACUCUGGCUGUAGGUGAAAAGUCUUGCCCUUCAAAGCUUGUGCUGUUGGGCUGUUCACAGUCUUCUCUUCAGUGUUGUCAAAUACCAACUGAUGUCCGUUUUUAUUUGAACUUUUUUGUUUUAAAUAAGAAAGAACAGCAAUGGUUAUUUGUAUAGCAUGACCAUGUACAAUUACCAAACCUCUCUGACCUUCACUGUCUCAAAAUAAUAUUUUAAAAGUAGUAGUAAAAAUUGCUCUCCUUUACAGAUAAAAUGUUCUCUGAUCAAGUGGAAUGAAAAUAAAAAUUAAUCCCAUGUUAAGUAAUCCAUAUGGAGACAAGAUGAAAAAGUGAUUGUCCUGCAAGUAAACAGACGAAAAAGGUCCCAGAAAGACCCACCCCCACCAAUCCAGCCCUGCUAAAAGUGAUUAUAACCUAUAAAGAAAGCCAGUGAAGUAUAAACUAUGUAUUUUCCAGGGUUACCAAAAGAUGCAUUUAUUUUAUCUUAUCAAAAGCGAAAAGUCGAAAAUAGCAAGGUUGUGUGUCUGCUGAAGAAGUGUUGCAAACUCUGGACAAAUAUUCAAAUAUUGAGAAGUCUUAAAGUGACAUAGUGCCAUGACAGUGUGAUUACAAGAAGAAUAAACACAUACAACAAAAGCAUGACAUUAGCACUUGCUAUGUCUGAGCGCAAGACUGCAAAAGCAAAGCAAAAUGAAAUACCUAGACAUGGUGGUACAAAUUGGUCCUAGAGCUGAAGCCAUUUAUUGGUAUCUUGGAUGGUUAACAUCUAAAUGCUUAAUUCCUGAAACCACUCAAGAGUCAUAGGAUUAGAUGAUCCAAGUCACCAAGAAAUUACUGUCUCAAGUGAUACGCUUCAGCGCCAGUCAGCAAAGUAAAUAAAUACUGUGCUUCUUCCAACUUUCAUUCCACUUGGGGAAAAAAAAAUAUCAUCAUGUCAAACAUUACGAUUGACCCAGAUGUCAAACCUGGUGAAUAUGUCAUCAAGAGCCUCUUUGCAGAAUUUGCUGUUCAAGCUGAAAAGAAAAUUGAAGUUGUAAUGGCCGAACCCUUGGAGAAGCUAUUGUCCAGAUCUCUUCAGAGGGGUGAAGAUCUUCAGUUUGAUCAGUUGAUAAGCUCUAUGAGCUCAGUAGCAGAGCACUGUCUCCCUUCCUUACUUCGCACCUUGUUUGACUGGUACAGACGCCAAAAUGGAACGGAAGAUGAAUCUUAUGAAUAUAGGCCUCGGUCUAGCACAAAGUCUAAGGGGGAUGAACAGCAACGUGAAAGAGAUUAUCUUCUUGAAAGGAGGGACUUAGCAGUAGACUUCAUUUUUUGUUUAGUUUUAGUUGAAGUUCUAAAGCAGAUUCCUGUUCAUCCUGUACCCGAUCCCUUAGUUCAUGAAGUUCUAAACUUAGCUUUUAAGCACUUUAAACAUAAGGAAGGAUAUUCAGGAACCAACACUGGGAAUGUGCAUAUUAUUGCUGAUUUAUAUGCAGAGGUGAUAGGGGUUCUUGCCCAAUCAAAGUUUCAGGCUGUAAGGAAGAAGUUUGUGACAGAAUUAAAAGAACUGCGACAAAAGGAACAAAGCCCACAUGUGGUACAAAGUGUCAUCAGCUUAAUAAUGGGAAUGAAAUUUUUUCGAGUAAAAAUGUAUCCUGUAGAAGAUUUUGAAGCAUCAUUUCAAUUUAUGCAGGAAUGUGCUCAGUAUUUCUUAGAAGUGAAAGAUAAAGAUAUAAAACAUGCACUUGCUGGUUUAUUUGUGGAGAUUCUUAUCCCUGUAGCUGCUGCUGUUAAAAAUGAAGUGAAUGUUCCCUGUUUGAAAAAUUUUGUGGAGAUGCUUUAUCAGACUACUUUUGAACUGAGCUCGAGAAAGAAGCAUUCAUUGGCUUUAUAUCCACUAAUUACCUGCCUUUUAUGUGUCAGUCAGAAACAAUUUUUUUUAAAUAACUGGCAUAUUUUCCUACAGAACUGUUUGUCACAUUUAAAGAUGCCAUCUAACAACAGUAUCAGAAAACAAAUAGAAACACUCCAGAAUAAAGAUCCGAAAAUGUCUCGAGUUGCACUGGAAUCUUUGUAUAGAUUAUUGUGGGUUUAUGUAAUUAGAAUAAAAUGUGAAAGCAACACUGUAACUCAAAGUCGUCUUAUGAGCAUAGUGUCAGCACUUUUUCCAAAAGGCUCACGAAGUGUGGUUCCUCGUGACACACCUCUCAAUAUAUUUGUGAAGAUUAUUCAGUUCAUUGCUCAGGAACGCUUGGAUUUUGCAAUGAAAGAAAUAAUAUUUGAUCUUCUCAGUGUUGGAAAAUCUACUAAAACUUUCACCAUUAAUCCAGAGAGAAUGAACAUAGGUCUCAGAGUCUUCCUUGUAAUAGCAGACAGUUUGCAGCAGAAAGAUGGUGAACCACCCAUGCCAACAACAGGAGUUAUUCUUCCCUCAGGAAAUACUCUUCGUGUAAAGAAAAUAUUUCUCAAUAAAACCUUGACAGAUGAAGAAGCAAAAGUCAUAGGAAUGUCAGUUUACUAUCCUCAAGUAAGAAAAGCAUUAGAUAGCAUCCUCAGACAUUUGGACAAAGAAGUUGGGAGACCAAUGUGUAUGACCAGUGUGCAGAUGUCUAAUAAGGAGCCUGAAGACAUGAUUACGGGGGAAAGAAAACCCAAGAUUGAUUUGUUUAGAACUUGUAUUGCUGCGAUUCCAAGGUUGAUUCCUGACGGUAUGAGCAGAACUGACCUGAUUGAAUUGUUAGCAAGGCUCACAAUUCAUAUGGAUGAAGAACUGCGUGCUCUGGCUUUCAAUACUCUGCAGGCACUAAUGCUUGAUUUUCCAGAUUGGCGGGAGGAUGUUCUUUCAGGAUUUGUUUAUUUUAUUGUUCGUGAAGUGACUGAUGUCCAUCCCACACUUCUUGAUAAUGCCGUAAAGAUGUUGGUACAAUUAAUAAAUCAGUGGAAACAAGCAGCCCAAAUGCAUAAUAAAAACCAGGACACUCAGCAUGGUGUAGCUAAUGGAGCUUCUCAUCCCCCUCCUCUGGAAAGGAGCCCAUAUUCCAAUGUAUUCCAUGUGGUUGAAGGCUUUGCGCUUGUCAUUCUCUGUAGCAGUCGACCUGCCACUAGGAGACUAGCCGUCAGUGUCCUUAGAGAAAUACGGGCUUUAUUUGCACUUCUGGAAAUACCUAAGGGUGAUGAUGAAUUAGCCAUAGAUGUGAUGGACAGGCUAAGCCCAUCCAUUCUUGAGAGCUUCAUACAUCUCACUGGGGCUGAUCAGACUACUUUGCUCUAUUGCCCUAGCUCGAUAGAUUUACAAACUUUAGCAGAAUGGAACUCUUCUCCUAUUAGCCACCAGUUUGAUGUGAUUAGUCCAUCACAUAUAUGGAUAUUUGCACAUGUGACCCAAGGCCAAGACCCAUGGAUUAUAAGUCUCUCCAGUUUUUUAAAGCAAGAAAAUCUUCCUAAACACUGCUCUACAGCUGUGAGCUAUGCUUGGAUGUUUGCAUACACAAGACUUCAGUUGUUGUCCCCUCAGGUCGAUAUAAAUAGCCCCAUCAAUGCUAAGAAAGUAAAUACCACCACAAGCAGUGACUCAUACAUUGGCCUGUGGAGAAACUAUCUGAUCCUUUGCUGCAGUGCAGCAACAUCGUCAUCUUCCACAUCUGCAGGUUCUGUGAGAUGUUCUCCUCCUGAGACGCUGGCGUCUACCCCAGAUAGCGGCUAUAGCAUUGAUUCUAAAAUUAUUGGCAUCCCAUCCCCUUCAUCCUUGUUUAAGCACAUAGUUCCAAUGAUGCGUUCUGAGAGCAUGGAAAUCACAGAAUCCCUUGUUCUAGGUCUUGGCAGGACCAACCCAGGAGCUUUUAGGGAACUAAUAGAGGAAUUACAUCCCAUAAUUAAAGAAGCACUCGAAAGAAGGCCAGAGAAUAUGAAACGGCGCAGGCGUCGAGACAUUUUACGAGUACAACUGGUACGAAUAUUUGAACUGCUGGCAGAUGCUGGUGUCAUUAGUCACAGUGCAAGUGGUGGCCUUGAUAAUGAAACACAUUUUCUCAACAACACUUUAUUGGAAUAUGUAGAUUUAACUAGACAACUCCUGGAAGCAGAAAAUGAAAAAGACUCUGACACACUGAAGGAUAUACGAUGCCAUUUUAGUGCCUUAGUGGCGAAUAUUAUUCAGAAUGUUCCAGUGCACCAGAGAAGAAGUAUUUUUCCUCAACAGAGCCUUCGUCACAGUCUAUUUAUGCUGUUCAGUCACUGGGCAGGUCCUUUUAGCAUCAUGUUUACGCCCUUGGACAGAUACAGUGAUAGAAAUAUGCAAAUUAAUAGACAUCAAUACUGUGCGUUAAAGGCUAUGUCUGCUGUACUGUGUUGUGGCCCUGUUGCAGAUAAUGUAGGACUUUCAUCAGAUGGCUAUUUGUACAAAUGGUUGGAUAACAUUUUGGAUUCUCUGGACAAAAAGGUUCACCAGCUGGGCUGUGAAGCAGUUACGUUGUUACUGGAGCUGAACCCUGAUCAGAGCAACCUGAUGUACUGGGCUGUGGACCGCUGCUACACGGGCUCCGGGAGGGUGGCGGCCGGCUGCUUUAAAGCCAUUGCUAAUGUUUUCCAGAACAGGGAUUAUCAAUGUGACACAGUGAUGCUUCUAAAUCUGAUACUGUUUAAAGCAGCUGAUUCUUCUAGAAGUAUCUAUGAAGUUGCUAUGCAACUUUUACAGAUUCUGGAACCGAAGAUGUUUCGCUAUGCUCACAAAUUGGAGGUUCAGAGAACAGAUGGAGUACUCAGCCAGCUGUCUCCUCUACCACAUCUCUAUUCUGUUUCAUAUUAUCAGUUGUCCGAGGAACUAGCAAGGGCGUAUCCUGAGCUAACUCUCGCCAUAUUCUCAGAGAUAAGCCAGAGAAUCCAGACAGCUCACCCUGCUGGGCGGCAGGUGAUGCUGCACUACCUGCUACCAUGGAUGAACAACAUCGAGCUGGUGGACUUAAAACCUCUCCCCACAGCAAGGCGACAUGAUGAAGAUGAAGAUGAUUCCUUAAAAGACCGAGAACUUAUGGUGACUAGUAGGCGCUGGUUACGGGGAGAAGGAUGGGGAUCUCCACAAGCCACUGCAAUGGUUUUGAACAAUCUGAUGUAUAUGACAGCAAAGUAUGGCGAUGAACUGGCCUGGUCGGAGGUGGAGAAUGUGUGGACCACACUUGCAGAUGGCUGGCCCAAAAACCUGAAAAUAAUUUUGCACUUUUUGAUCAGCAUUUGUGGGGUGAAUAGCGAACCAAGCCUCUUGCCUUACGUGAAGAAGGUCAUUGUAUAUUUAGGUAGAGAUAAAACAAUGCAGUUGCUAGAAGAGCUGGUGAGUGAGCUUCAGCUGACCGAUCCUGUCAGUUCAGGGGUCACUCACAUGGAUAAUCCCCCGUAUUAUCGCAUCACUUCCAGCUAUAAAAUCCCUUCUGUCACCUCAGGAACUACUUCCAGUAGCAAUACAAUGGUAGCUCCCACAGAUGGCAAUCCUGAUAAUAAGCCCAUUAAAGAGAAUAUUGAAGAGAGCUAUGUGCACCUGGACAUUUACAGUGGACUAAACAGUCAUUUGAAUCGGCAACAUCACAGACUAGAAUCCCGAUACAGUAGCAGCUCUGGAGGAUCUUAUGAAGAAGAAAAAAGUGAUUCAAUGCCACUUUAUUCUAAUUGGCGACUGAAAGUGAUGGAGCAUAACCAAGGAGAGCCACUGCCCUUCCCACCAGCUGGAGGCUGCUGGUCACCACUGGUGGAUUACGUGCCUGAAACGUCAUCACCUGGAUUACCUCUUCACAGGUGUAACAUAGCAGUGAUCCUUUUGACUGAUCUCAUCAUUGAUCAUAGUGUGAAGGUGGAAUGGGGAAGCUACCUCCAUCUUCUUCUUCAUGCAAUUUUUAUAGGGUUUGACCACUGCCACCCUGAGGUGUAUGAACAUUGUAAACGCCUGCUUCUGCACUUAUUAAUAGUAAUGGGACCCAAUAGUAACAUCCGAACUGUUGCUUCUGUCCUUCUCAGGAACAAGGAGUUUAAUGAGCCCAGGGUGCUUACAGUCAAACAAGUUGCACACUUAGAUUAUAAUUUCACAGCAGGCAUUAACGAUUUUAUACCUGAUUACCAGCCCUCCCCUAUGACUGACUCAGGGCUUAGCUCAAGUUCUACCUCUUCUAGUAUCAGCUUAGGAAAUAACAGUGCUGCCAUUUCACAUCUGCACACCACUAUCCUCAAUGAGGUUGACAUCUCAGUGGAGCAGGAUGGAAAAGUCAAAACCCUCAUGGAAUUCAUUACCUCAAGAAAAAGAGGGCCCCUUUGGAACCAUGAGGAUGUUUCUGCCAAGAAUCCUAGCAUAAAGAGUGCUGAACAGUUAACUACAUUUUUGAAACAUGUGGUUUCUGUUUUUAAGCAGUCAAGCUCAGAAGGAAUUCAUCUGGAACAUCAUCUUAGUGAAGUUGCUCUGCAAACAGCACUUUCCUGUUCUUCUCGACACUAUGCUGGGAGAUCCUUUCAGAUUUUCAGGGCCCUAAAGCAGCCUCUCACUGCAACUACACUUUCUGAUGUUCUCUCCAGACUUGUAGAAACUGUAGGGGAUCCAGGAGAAGAUGCACAGGGAUUUGUGAUUGAGCUUCUUCUCACAUUGGAAUCUGCAAUUGAUACUUUGGCUGAAACCAUGAAGCAUUAUGAUCUUCUUUCUGCCCUUUCUCAAACCUCAUAUCAUGAUCCUAUAAUGGGAAACAAGUAUGCAGCUAACAGGAAAAGCACUGGACAACUCAAUCUAAGCACAAGUCCCAUUAAUAGUAGCAGUUAUUUGGGAUAUAACAGUAAUGCAAGAAGUAACUCUUUGAGAUUAAGUUUGAUUGGUGACCGACGAGGUGACCGGCGGCGGAGUAACACACUGGAUAUAAUGGAUGGACGGAUAAACCAUAGCAGUAGUUUAGCAAGGACUAGAAGCCUUUCCUCUCUAAGAGAGAAAGGAAUGUAUGACGUGCAGUCCACUACUGAGCCUACCAACUUGAUGGCCACCAUUUUUUGGAUAGCAGCAUCUUUAUUAGAAUCAGAUUAUGAAUAUGAAUACCUCCUGGCUCUCAGGCUUCUCAACAAACUGCUUAUCCAUUUGCCUUUGGAUAAAUCAGAGAGUCGAGAGAAGAUUGAAAAUGUACAAAGCAAAUUGAAAUGGACUAAUUUUCCAGGACUUCAGCAGCUCUUCCUUAAGGGUUUUACCUCAGCAUCUACACAAGAAAUGACCGUGCACCUCCUCAGUAAACUCAUUUCUGUCUCCAAACAUACAUUGGUGGAUCCUUCCCAAUUGUCAGGCUUUCCUCUUAACAUCCUUUGCUUAUUGCCUCACUUAAUCCAGCAUUUUGACAGCCCAACUCAGUUUUGCAAAGAAACAGCUAGUCGAAUAGCAAAGGUUUGUGCAGAAGAAAAAUGCCCAACACUUGUCAAUCUGGCACACAUGAUGAGUUUGUACAGUACACACACGUAUUCCAGAGACUGUUCUAACUGGAUCAAUGUCGUGUGCAGAUACCUGCAUGACUCCUUCUCAGAUACAACAUUUAAUCUUGUGACUUAUCUUGCAGAGCUGUUAGAGAAAGGAUUGUCCAGUAUGCAGCAAUCAUUACUACAGAUUAUUUAUAGUCUAUUGAGUCAUAUUGACCUGUCUGCAGCCCCAGCCAAGCAGUUUAAUCUGGAGAUCAUAAAGAUUAUUGGCAAAUAUGUACAGAGUCCUUACUGGAAGGAAGCCCUUAACAUAUUAAAGCUGGUGGUGUCACGCUCUGCGAGUCUUGUCGUACCCAGUGAUAUCCCCAAGACCUAUGGAGGAGAUACAGGUUCUCCUGAAAUAUCCUUCACUAAAAUUUUUAAUAAUGUUUCUAAGGAGUUGCCUGGGAAGACCUUAGAUUUUCAUUUUGAUAUAUCUGAGACACCAAUUAUUGGAAACAAAUAUGGUGAUCAGCACAGUGCGGCUGGAAGAAAUGGGAAACCAAAAGUUAUUGCUGUCACUAGAAGUACUUCCUCAACUUCUUCUGGUUCUAAUUCUAAUGCCUUGGUUCCUGUUAGUUGGAAAAGGCCACAGUUAUCACAGCGAAGAACAAGAGAAAAGCUAAUGAAUGUGCUUUCUCUCUGUGGUCCAGAAUCUGGCCUCCCAAAGAACCCAUCAGUUGUAUUUUCUUCUAAUGAGGAUUUGGAAGUCGGUGACCAACAGACUAGCCUAAUUUCUACAACAGAAGACAUAAAUCAAGAGGAAGAAGUAGCUGUGGAAGAUAAUAGCAGUGAACAACAGUUUGGUGUUUUUAAGGAUUUUGACUUUUUAGAUGUUGAAUUGGAAGAUGCAGAGGGUGAAAGUAUGGACAAUUUCAACUGGGGAGUUCGCAGGCGCUCACUGGACAGUAUUGACAAAGGGGACACUCCAUCCCUCCAGGAGUACCAGUGCUCUAGUAGCACCCCCAGCCUGAACCUCACCAAUCAGGAGGAUACAGAUGAGUCCUCGGAAGAAGAAGCGGCACUUACAGCAAGCCAGAUACUCUCACGCACACAGAUGUUAAACAGUGAUUCUGCCACUGAUGAAACAAUACCAGACCAUCCUGACUUACUUCUCCAGUCUGAAGAUUCCACUGGCAGCAUCACAACAGAGGAAGUGCUUCAAAUCAGGGAUGAGACCCCAACUUUGGAGGCUUCUCUAGAUAAUGCUAACAGCCGGCUGCCUGAGGAUACAACUUCAGUAUUAAAGGAGGAACAUGUUACAACCUUUGAAGAUGAAGGAUCCUAUAUAAUUCAAGAACAGCAGGAAUCUCUUGUGUGUCAAGGAAUUCUUGAUUUAGAAGAAACUGAAAUGCCAGAGCCUCUAGCUCCUGAAAGUUACCCCGAGUCAGUCUGUGAAGAGGAUGUUACCUUAGCUCUGAAAGAGCUAGAUGAAAGAUGUGAAGAAGAAGAAGCGGAUUUCUCCGGACUGUCUAGUCAAGAUGAAGAAGAGCAAGAUGGUUUUCCAGAAGUACAGACGUCGCCUCUGCCGUCACCAUUUCUUUCUGCCAUCAUAGCCGCCUUUCAGCCCGUGGCAUAUGAUGAUGAAGAGGAAGCCUGGCGCUGCCACGUCAAUCAGAUGCUGUCUGACACCGACGGGUCCUCUGCAGUGUUUACUUUUCAUGUGUUUUCUAGGCUGUUUCAGACAAUUCAAAGAAAGUUUGGAGAAAUAACUAAUGAGGCAGUCAGCUUUCUUGGUGAUAGUCUGCAACGCAUUGGUACCAAAUUUAAAAGUUCCUUGGAAGUGAUGAUGCUGUGUUCAGAAUGCCCAACAGUCUUUGUGGAUGCUGAAACACUGAUGUCAUGUGGUUUGCUGGAAACACUCAAGUUUGGUGUUUUGGAGUUGCAAGAACACCUGGAUACAUACAAUGUGAAAAGAGAAGCCGCUGAGCAGUGGCUAGAUGAUUGUAAGAGGACAUUUGGUGCCAAAGAAGACAUGUAUAGGAUAAACACAGAUGCACAACAAAUGGAAAUACUAGCAGAAUUGGAGCUCUGCCGAAGAUUAUACAAAUUGCAUUUUCAAUUGCUGCUUCUGUUCCAGGCCUACUGUAAACUUAUCAACCAAGUAAAUACGAUAAAAAAUGAAGCAGAGGUCAUCAACAUGUCAGAGGAACUUGCCCAACUGGAAAGUAUCCUCAAAGAAGCUGAGUCCGCUUCCGAAAACGAAGAAAUUGACAUUUCCAAAGCUGCACAAACUACUAUAGAAACUGCCAUUCAUUCUUUAAUUGAAACUUUGAAAAAUAAAGAAUUUAUAUCAGCUGUAGCACAAGUCAAAGCUUUCAGAUCUCUCUGGCCCAGUGAUAUCUUUGGCAGUUGUGAAGAUGACCCUGUACAGACACUGUUACAUAUAUAUUUCCAUCAUCAGACGCUGGGCCAGACAGGAAGCUUUGCAGUUAUAGGCUCUAACCUGGACAUGUCAGAAGCCAACUACAAACUGAUGGAACUUAAUCUGGAAAUAAGAGAGUCUCUACGCAUGGUGCAAUCAUACCAACUUCUAGCACAGGCCAAACCAAUGGGAAAUAUGGUGAGCACUGGAUUCUGAGACACUUCAGGCCUUUAGGAAAGAAACUAAACUGAAGAUGAUGAAGAAUAUUAACCAAGCACCUUUUAUGGACCCUUGCAUUCACUGAUAACUUUCUGGCAGCAUCUACUUUUUAGUGUAACUAAUGUCAAACUGUAUCAUCAAAAACAAAGAUCUGAAAGAAAAAAACAUCUGAUAUUUUAACAGCUGCCAAUAUCUCCCACAAUAACUGCGUGAAGAAGGAAUUUUUUAAUUACUUAACCUACGUGAAAAGAAAAGGGCUAAAAGUGAUGCCUACAAAUACAUUACUUUCUGGGGAAAGAAAAGAAUUCCAAGAAUGUUUGCAAUAAUGGCCUCCAAUACUGAAACAACCAAAAGCAGGUGAAAUGAGGCUGAAAUCAAGGCUGUUUCAUUUUAGCUGAAGACCUGCAAAGCUGCUUGGAUUUCUAGCAGUUGAAAACCUAACCUGCAAUUGAUGCUUAAUCAUCCAUCCACAUGAACAUGCAGUCAGCUAUACGCAUCAAGACUCGUUUGCAAAAACCAUUGAUUUUUCAGUAUGUGGGAUAAGGGUUUGGGUUUUUUUGUUUUUUGGUCUGUAUAAGGAAUUAUGUGUGUGUGAGUUGGGAUGUAUGGAUAUGUGAUAGUCAUAUUUUCAAGGUAUGGAUGUUUGGUGAUAACGUCUCAGAGCAUGCCUAAAAGAGCACUGCAAGAUUAUUUUUGAAGAAAUGUUAUUUUAUUAGAUCUAACUCUUCAUAGUAUGUAAAUGUUAGAACAUUUUAAUAAUAUUUUAAAACUGGGCUUUCCCAGUAUUUCAAAAAGAAAUAAUAUAUCUGUUAACGUUAUUGGAAUGCUGCUCAGUUCUCUGAUCAGUGCUUAUGUUAUGAUUGUUGAUAACUAACCAAAGUAGAUGCCUGCAGAGACUUUAAAAUGUAAAAUAAAGAUGUAUGCUGCCUGUCAGCUAUUCUCAUUAGAAAAGUUUUAACUUAUUUUACUCCAUAUAGAAACUGUAGAGACUAAAACCAGUUAUUUUCUUGUACAUUUGUGCCAUGCACUGUUGUUAUACAAGAAUAGGUGUACAAAGCUAAAGAAAAAUUGUGGUCAUUGAUGAUGGAAUAUAUGACUUGCAGGCUUUGAAGUCUGCAGAAUUCAAGAAAAGAGCUGCAAAUGCAUUUUUGUAUCUUUAUUCAGGACUCACAUGCUUUACCCUAAAGAAACCUGGGGCUAGGGGAAAUGAAAGGAAGCCUGAAGACUGACUACCAAAACAUGCAAUAUACUUAUUCACUGUCUAAGUCUGUAGUAUAACAUGAACUGGAGUCUCUAUCCUUUUCUAAAAUCGCAUUUUGUAAGAAAAGAAAGAAAAAAAAAAAAAAAGAAUGUAGUCCCACAACUCCUGAUUUGAAAGAAACACCUUGUAUUUUUUAUAUACAUCUCUUAUCCACUGUGACUUUUCUUUUAAACUGGGCUCUGUGAUUCCAGAGUUUAGAAUGUAGAAAUGAAAUGCUUAGCUUUACCUUUUCUUGGGGGGUGUGGACCCUGCCAGAAAUGUAAUUACGUAUGCUCAAGUGCAUUAAUUGAAGGCACUGUGCACACCAUUGGACUGCUGACCACAGUUAAACAUUUCCAGUAAAAUUUCGUAACUGGUCACAGCUCAUUCAUAAUCACUGUAUUUUUUGACCCUGAUAAAGACAAUUAUUUUGAUGGUGUUCUGGUACUGUAAUUGGUAUCCUUUAAAUUAUUUAAAACUUUUGGGUGUGGGGCAGGCAGAGAGGGAUGGUGUCCAGAGAUACAUCACACUUUACAUCCUAUCUUACUGUCCUCUGUUUUUCUUACCCUCCUUACAUCCUUUUUGUUAAAAAUAAAAAGCAUUGUAGCUGUUGGUUUGUGUUGUAUUUUAACAAAGAAUGAAUGAUUACAGUGUGCAUCAUUUAGAAACCUUUCAAAUGUUACCUUCUUGAAUUGCCCUAGAAAAGAACAAAAUUAGUUGACUACCCAACCAAACCUUUCAGUUGAUAUUUGCUUUUUGUGUUUAUUUAUAUGUAACUAAGUCUAUUAAUAUAAUAAAAAUGAAUAUACCUGCAGCAAGCAA